ACAACGAGAAGCCACCGGAAGCGGAAGCCAGGUAUGGCGUUCGGGGCCCGGGAGUCUGGGCAAUACAGUUUUGUGCUCACUGGGUGAAGAGGCUGACUUAGGGCGGGGAAAGGAGGGAGCCAGGCUGGAUCUCUUUCCGCAGCUCUCCUCACGUUCCCCUCUAGUCCCGGCGCGGCGCUGCUGCCCAGGGGACUGGCCUAUCCUCGGCCAAUCCGCUGGGUCCUUAUUGCCUGUUGGGCCCCUAGUGCGAAUCAGUCCCGCCAGAGACCCUUGACGGGCAUACUGUUUCCUCCGGGCUCCUGCCUCAUGAGGGGAGAGGUGCGGCUUGGCUCCGUGCGUAGGGACUUGGGUGGGGUGGGGUGGGCGGUGUGAGAACUGGAACGUCCCAGUGCGCUAACCUGAGGUGGUGCCAGCCAUUCUGCUCGUCCCUUUGCACUUCUCCAUUUCCCCUUAGGCUCUAAGUGUGACCUUCGAACCCUGGUCAGAGUAAUGGUGAGGGGCAGGCGUGACGUUAUUUCAUUACACGGCUUCUCGGCAUUCCACAGGUUUCCCUCCGCCUCCUGAGGGCCUUUCCUAACCCACAGAGUGGAUUCCUGGCUCCAGAAAAUGGGCUUGGAGCGGGGGCCACGUUGAGGAAGGCGAAGGGCAUUGUGGGGGCGUUAUGUAAAAGUAGGACCCCAACCGACAGAUCCUAGUGCUCGCGCCACCUGGGCGCGCGGAGCUUUGCUCGUUUACUAUUGAAAAAGUUCCAGCGCGGGAAACUGAACCCGGAGCUUUGCGCACGCCCGAGCCCUCAAGUAAUAAUGGCGCCAUUUUGCGGUACGGAAGCUACACAGCAACACGUAUAGGAGACUCUCCCCGAGAUCUUCUAGGGAGUGACCCAUCUAUUUUUGUUUGGGAAGAGGAAACUCCGAAAUGGGAUCGCGGAAGACUUAAAGGGCCAGGCUGAUUUUUUUUUCCUACUGCAGGUCUCUGAGGCUGUGGUUGCUACAGGGUCACCACGAGCUUGGCUUACUUGUCUCAUCCUUCCCUUGCCUGGUAUCAUUUUCUCAGUUCUCCCAAAAGCCAUGUCCCGGCCCUUGCUCAUCACCUUCACCCCAGCCACUGACCCCAGCGACCUCUGGAAGGAUGGGCAGCAGCAGCCACAGCCCGAGAAGCCAGAGUCCACCCUGGAUGGGGCUGCAGCCCGAGCUUUCUAUGAGGCCCUGAUUGGGGAUGAGAGCAGCGCUCCUGACUCCCAGAGAUCUCAGACUGAACCUGCCAGAGAAAGAAAGAGAAAGAAAAGAAGAAUAAUGAAGGCACCAGCAGCAGAAGCAGUGGCAGAAGGAGCAUCAGGAAGACAUGGACAAGGGAGAUCCCUUGAGGCUGAGGAUAAGAUGACUCACCGGAUACUGAGGGCAGCCCAGGAGGGGGACCUGCCAGAACUUAGGAGACUGCUGGAACCGCAUGAGGCAGGAGGAGCUGGGGGGAAUAUCAACGCCCGGGAUGCCUUCUGGUGGACCCCACUGAUGUGUGCUGCUCGAGCGGGCCAGGGGGCAGCUGUGAGCUAUCUCCUGGGCCGUGGGGCUGCCUGGGUGGGGGUCUGUGAGCUGAGUGGCAGGGAUGCGGCUCAGCUCGCUGAAGAAGCUGGCUUCCCUGAGGUAGCCCGCAUGGUCAGGGAGAGCCAUGGAGAGACAAGGAGCCCGGAAAACCGGUCUCCUACUCCCUCCCUCCAGUACUGCGAGAACUGUGACACCCACUUCCAAGAUUCCAACCACCGCACAUCCACUGCUCACCUGCUGUCACUGUCGCAGGGUCCUCAGCCUCCCAACCUUCCACUUGGGGUGCCCAUCUCCAGCCCGGGCUUCAAACUGCUGCUGAGGGGGGGCUGGGAGCCAGGAAUGGGGCUGGGACCCCGGGGUGAGGGCCGUGCCAAUCCCAUCCCCACUGUCCUCAAGAGGGACCAGGAAGGACUAGGCUACAGAUCAGCACCCCAGCCCCGAGUGACACAUUUCCCAGCUUGGGAUACCCGAGCUGUGGCUGGGAGGGAGAGACCCCCUCGGGUGGCCACACUGAGCUGGAGGGAGGAGAGAAGGAGGGAGGAGAAAGACAGGGCUUGGGAGCGGGAUCUAAGGACUUACAUGAACCUCGAGUUCUGACUUUGGUAAAGUCUGACCCUAGUCUGCUGCUGAAGUCUGAACUUGGGCCUCUGACCUGGGCCCUUUGACUUCCCCUUCCUGGGAUCUGCUCAGAUGCAGAUCCUGAAGUUUUUGGUCAAUAGGCUCUGUCUUCGUGAGAGACGGGCUGAGAGUCAGAAAUAAAUCAACCAUUUGUGGUUUAUUCACUUUUCUGGAAGCUAUUUUGAGGAAGCCAAACAGAAGCCUGGGAGCCACAUGCAAGUCCCACCUGAGUCAGAAGGGGCAGCCUCUCCAGGUGGCAUGAUAAGGUCACCUCCCUGCCAAUCUGGGUUCACUUUCAGGUCCCAGACCCUCCUGGGAGUCCCCCACCUAUUCUUUCAACCCCCCUGGACCAAGAAUUGCCCAGCUUCGUGCAAGUCUCACUUCCCCCAGGAGGAGUUCCCUGACUACAGCCAAUUCACUGAUUUCACAAACAUAAGUCCAUAUACUAUGUGCCAAGAAUACAGGUAAAGACAUUCCCAACCCUCAAAGAGUUCACAGCUGGAGAGGGAAAGUGCCAUGUUAUCAAUUUUUUUCUUUUUUUUUUGAGAUGCAGUUUCGCUCUCAUUGCCCAGGCUGGAGUGCAAUGGCAUGAUCUCGGCUCACCACAACCUCUGCCCCCCGAGUUCAAGGGAUUCUCCUGCCUCAGCCUCCCCAGUAGCUGGGAUUACAGGCAUGCCCCACCACGCCCAGCUAAUUUUGUAUUUUUAGUAGAGACGGGGUUUCUCCAUGUUGGCCAAGCUGGUCUUGAACUCCCGACCUCAGGUGAUCCGCCGGCCUCGGCUUCCCAAAGUGCUGGGGUUGCAGGCAUGAGCCACCACUCCCGGCCCAUGUUAUCAAAUAUUAUAAUGCAGGGUGAUAAGGGAAGUCAAGGCCUCUAGAGAUGAGAAUGGGUAGGGUUUUGCUGGAAGAGGCCAGUGUGAUAGGAAGGCCCACGAUUAUCAAGCUUGUACACUUAGUUGAACUGGGACCAGAACUCUAGCCCCCAAAUCUAAACUUUAAACUUCUUUGUUCCACCCA